CUGCACCGUCAUCUCCUGCCCCGCCGAGGCUUGACCCGUGCUGUCCCCCUCUCCCUUCCUUUGCCCACCGAUUGGAGGGACACUCUGGAAAACUCAGUUGAAGAAAGCGGAGAGUCUGCGUGUACACAGUGCAAUGAUGUCAGUUAAUGCACUAGUGAGGGCAUGUGUUGUUCACGGUACACAGAAGAAGGAACCACCAGCCCUUGGGACACUUAGGCAUUGGUGUAGACAAGGGAACAUUUGAGUCCUGGACGAUGGAUAGGUCCACGGAGCGGAGGGAGGAGAAAAGGAUUCCAGUCUUAGCGAUCAGCAUCAGCAAAGGCUCCGAGGUGCCAGAGGCAUAGUGAGUUCUCCGAUCCCUGGCUGGUGGAGGGAAGCUGGGAAGGGCCUGGCUGUCCAGGGUGGUGGGAGGAGGCUAGAGUAGCCAGACCAGAUAUUUUGGGUUGUCUCUGAUGGGCAGUGGGGUGUGGGGGGGAGGUAGAUAGGUAUUUAGGAUGGAAUUCUGCUAGACAGGAAAAUAUAGUUCAGUUCCUCAUAGUUCAGGCUGGAGCAAGUAAGAUUCCAGUUUUACCACUGAAUCUCUGAGCCUGUCUCCUCAUCUGUAAAAUGGGAACAGCAAUCCUAGCCCAGAGGGUUGUCAAAGUCACUGUGCUAUCGGGCCUGGCAGAAUGGGAGUGAGAGGGGCUCAGAGGGACUGUUACAGGACAUGAGGUGACGAUGGUGGGGUGGCAAGGCAGGAGCUGAUGGAGACUCACUGAGAAGUGGAGAAGCAAGAUUCAUCACAUACGGGACAUAAAGGGAGAUGGAGGGGCAGGGGGUAGUCCUGGUCUCGGCCUGGUGGGGAAGGGCUUCAAUGGGAGGAAGCCAGGGUGUGAAGUGACGGGGGAGGUAUAGUGUGACACCAGAGGGUACUGAGAAAGACCUGGGAGGCAGGAUGGCGGCUAGGACUAAAUCCUCUCUCCCAGAGAAGGCCGAGCCUCCUAGAGCCAGAGAAGGAGGCAGAGGAGGGACAGCAAAGGGAAGAAGAGAUGGGAGGAUGCCGUGUGAACAAAGCCAAGGCGGGGAGGAGAAGAAGUUAUUAUCAGGGUGGGGGUGGGCUGAGGGCAUGGUUCAAGGCCUGAUGUCUUUGCCUCCUAAUGCCGGGGGUCUUGCUGGCUGGGUCAGGCCACUCACAGGAAUGGGCCAUAAUCCUUGGUUGACAAUAAAUGGACAAAGCAGCUGGGUGCGGUGGCUCAUGCCUGUAAUCCCAACACUUUGGGAGGCCAAGGUGGGUGGAUCACGAGGUCAGGAGUUCGAGACCAGCCUAGCCAACAUAGUGAAACCCCGUCUCAACUAAAAACACAAAAAAUUAGCUGAGCGUGGUGCGGGCACCUGUAAUCUCAGCUACUCGGGAGGCUGAGGCAGAAGAAUCGCUUGAACUCAGGAGGCAGAGGUUGCAGUGAUGAGAGAAUGUGCCACUGCACUCCAGCCUGGGCAACAGAGUGAGACUCUGUCAAAAAAAAAAAAAAAAAAUGGAUAAAGCAGAUUGACUCUCCCUAAUAGCCGCUGUUGGUAGAGAUAGUCUCUCAAGAGCCAGGCAUGGUGGUUCACAUGGUGGUUCACAAAGUGCUGGUAAUCCCAGCACUUUGGAAGGCUGAGAUGGGAGGAUUGCUUGAGGCCAGCAGUUCGAGACCAGCCUGAUCAAUAUAGCAAGACCAGGACAGGCGCGGUGGCUCACGCCUGUAAUCCCAGCACUUUGGGAGGCCAAGGCAGGUGGAUCACGAGGUCAGGAGUUCAAGACCAGCCUGGCCAACAUAGUGAAACCCCGUCUCCACUAAAAUAAAUAAAUACAAAAAAUAUAUAUAGCAAGACCCCACCUCUAAAAAAAAAAAAAAAAAAAAAGGCUGGGCACGAGAAUCACUUGAGCCUGGGAGGCGGAGGUUGCAGUGAGCCAAGAUUGCGCCACUGCACUCCAGCUUGGGCAACAGCGAGACUCCAUCUCAAAAAAAAAAAAAAAAAAGUCUCUCAAAAUAGUGCGAUCCAUGGAGGAAAAUCAGUCCAAGUUCGGCAAGUAUUUGUCGGUAUCCUGUAUGAGCUAGGCCUUGGGUACUUCAAGAUCAAACAACAAAUGUCUGUAGGUAAUUCCCAGGUCAGCAGGGAGCCAGGUGGGUCAGCAGAGAGACAGUCACAUUAGGAGUUAGGGCUUCAGUAGGGAGACAGGUGGGUCUCAGGUGAUGUCAAGAGAUCUUGGUCAGAGCUAGGCCUGAAGAAGAUUCUGGUAUCUCUGCUCAGGAAUCAGGGGACCAGGAAGGGCCAGGAGACUACAUUGGGGUUGCACUAUGGUGGUGGUGUUGGUGGGAGGGUGUAGAGGCGGGGCUUGUCCUGGAAAGUUGGAUAUCAGGGUCAAGGUAAGGGGAGAGGGGCAGGGAGGCUCUCAGCACUUUGUGCUCUGGGUUCAGAGGGGACUGGAGGAUAGAGUAUGGAAGCAGGGAGCUCUGAUCCUGGGUUCUGCAGGGCCAAAGCAGGAGGCAGAAGGCUGGACUUAGUAAGUGGUGAGGAUGGUGAGAGAAAUAUUCAGCAGUCAGACUGGAAAGGACUUGUCUGCAAGCUGGGUGUGGAGUAUCAGCAUCAAUCCUAGGUUUUUCUGCCUGGUUAGGUGGGGAAGCAGAUUUGAGAGAAAGACCUUAGUUUGGAUAAACGGGGUCUGAACUCGCCUCGGAUUUGCCGGGGGUGGAGCUCAGGACGUCCUGGUUGGGGAGGGCAUUCAGAGAGUAGAUGCCAGUCCUGGGAAAGGCAGGGGAGGAGAGGAGAGCCACGGCUGACGCUUGGGGACAGAAGGAGGAGCCUGAGGAGGAGACAGGACAGAGCGUCUGGAGAGGCAGGAGGACACCGAGUUCCCCGUGUUGGCCUCCAGGUCCUGUGCUUGCGGAGCCGUCCGGCGGCUGGGAUCGAGCCCCGACAAUGGGCAACGCGCAGGAGCGGCCGUCAGAGACUAUCGACCGCGAGCGGAAACGCCUGGUCGAGACGCUGCAGGCGGACUCGGGACUGCUGUUGGACGCGCUGCUGGCGCGGGGCGUGCUCACCGGGCCAGAGUACGAGGCAUUGGAUGCACUGCCUGAUGCCGAGCGCAGGGUGCGCCGCCUACUGCUGCUGGUGCAGGGCAAGGGCGAGGCCGCCUGCCAGGAGCUGCUACGCUGUGCCCAGCGUACCGCGGGCGCGCCGGACCCCGCUUGGGACUGGCAGCACGUGGGUCCGGGCUACCGGGACCGCAGCUAUGACCCUCCAUGCCCAGGCCACUGGACGCCGGAGGCACCCGGCUCGGGGACCACAUGCCCCGGGUUGCCCAGAGCUUCAGACCCUGACGAGGCCGGGGGCCCUGAGGGCUCCGAGGCGGUGCAAUCCGGGACCCCGGAGGAGCCAGAGCCAGAGCUGGAAGCUGAGGCCUCUAAAGAGGCUGAACCGGAGCCGGAGCCAGAGCCAGAGCUGGAACCCGAGGCUGAAGCAGAACCAGAGCCGGAACUGGAGCCAGAACCGGACCCAGAGCCCGAGCCCGACUUCGAGGAAAGGGACGAGUCCGAAGAUUCCUGAAGGCCAGAGCUCUGACAGGCGGUGCCCCGCCCAUGCUGGAUAGGACCUGGGAUGCUGCUGGAGCUGAAUCGGAUGCCACCAAGGCUCGGUCCAGCCCAGUACCGCUGGAAGUGAAUAAACUCCGGAGGGUCGGACGGGACCUGGGCUCUCUCCACGAUUCUGGCUGUUUGCCCAGGAACUUAGGGUGGGUACCUCUGAGUCCCAGGGACCUGGGCAGGCCCAAGCCCACCACGAGCAUCAUCCAGUCCUCAGCCCUAAUCUGCCCUUAGGAGUCCAGGCUGCACCCUGGAGAUCCCAAACCUAGCCCCCUAGUGGGACAAGGACCUGACCCUCCUGCCCGCAUACACAACCCAUUUCCCCUGGUGAGCCACUUGGCAGCAUAUGUAGGUACCAGCUCAACCCCACGCAAGUUCCUGAGCUGAACAUGGAGCAAGGGGAGGGUGACUUCUCUCCACAUAGGGAGGGCUUAGAGCUCACAGCCUUGGGAAGUGAGACUAGAAGAGGGGAGCAGAAAGGGACCUUGAGUAGACAAAGGCCACACACAUCAUUGUCAUUACUGUUUUAAUUGUCUGGCUUCUCUCUGGACUGGGAGCUCAGUGAGGAUUCUGACCAGUGACUUACACAAAAGGCGCUCUAUACAUAUUAUAAUAUAUUCGCUUACUAAAUGAAUAAGGACUUUCCAA